GAGAAAUCCGCGCGCAGCCUCCGCCGCUGCACACUGCAGCCUCUGCUGAACCCCUGCCGCGCCGCCGCCUUCGCCAGCCCGGACCGGACCGGCCCGCCUUCCCUUCCUCCGCUCCAGCCGGCCUCCGGCCCCGCAACCUCCUCCUCGGCGAAGUCUCCCUGGCCGCCCCAUGUCGGCCGCCCCCGCCUACAGCGAAGACAAGGGCGGCUCCGCUGGCCCCGGGGAGCCCGAGUACGGCCACGACCCCGCGAGCGGCGGCAUCUUCUCCUCCGACUACAAGCGGCAUGAUGACCUGAAGGAGAUGCUGGACACCAACAAGGAUUCUCUCAAGCUGGAGGCCAUGAAGAGGAUUGUGGCGAUGAUUGCCCGAGGAAAGAAUGCUUCAGACCUGUUUCCCGCGGUGGUGAAGAACGUGGCCUGUAAGAACAUAGAGGUGAAGAAGCUUGUCUAUGUGUACCUGGUACGCUACGCUGAGGAGCAGCAAGACCUGGCCCUGCUGUCCAUCUCCACCUUCCAACGUGGCCUAAAGGAGCCUGUGGUAAUGGCUGCUUCUAGUAUGAACCACUUGAGCCCCCGGAGAGUGGAGAGUCUCUAGCAAUGGAGAACCCCUCAACCCUCACCCCCCUUUGUGUAAAGGUGUGAAUUGUGGUCCACAGCCAGGUAGAUUUCAACCUUUAGCAGUGGCCUGAAUCCCCCACACCAUUCUCACCUUUUGUUUCAUUUUGCCCAAGGCCUCUAGUUGGAUUUACAUAUGUUAGGUGCAUGUAUAAGUCUCCCCCCUAAGGGCUUUUCUGGUUAGUCUAAGACAUCUUGAGGGUAAAGACAGCCAUUUCAAGGCCAUUCUCUCCAUAUUGGAUUUUUCAGCUCUGAUUACAACCAUUAACUCCUCUAUUUUUGCAUACCUUUAUUUAUUUAUUUAUUUAUGAGACAGGUUCUCACUGUGUUGCCCAGGCUGGAGUGCAGUGGUGCAAUCAUGGCUCACUGGAGCCUCGACUUCCCUGAGCUCAGGUGAUUCUCCCACCUCUGUCUCCUGAGUAGCUGCGACUACUCAGCCUGCAUCACCAUGCUCGGCUAAUUUUUUUGUAGUUUUUGUAGAGAUGGGGUUUCACCCUGUUGCCUAUGCUGGUCUUGGACUCCUGGGCUCAAGUGGCCUCAGCUUCCCAAAGUGCUGGGAUUACAGGGAUGAGCUAAUACUCCUAGCCUGGAUACUUUUAGUUCAAAUUUCUGUGAGAGAGAUUGUGAAAGGUCCAGCUCAUCUUUUCAUAUCCAGAAGUUCUGUAGGUUGCUGGGUAGACAGGAUUGCUGCUCAAAUCCAGGGCCCACCCCUUGUCCAAUCUGCUAUGGCCAGCAAGAGGGGUUGACAGUCGGCUUCUUUGGGGUGAGAGUAGAAAGCAUGGUCACUUGAAUAUACAAUUCAUUCAUUUAGUAAAUACUUGGGUGUCUCUAUGCCACACAUUGUGCUAGAUUUCUUUUUAUAAGUCAAAACCAUGGAAUCCGUCUUAGAUUGGCAAGUAAUCUUUUGGUUUGAGUAAGGGUUAAGUAUAAAAACUAAUCUGAAAUUGUUGUACAGAUUUUCACCUAUAGUCUCUACCAACUGACCCUGUCCCCCUUUUAGAAAACCAGAGCUCAUUUAGUUCAACUCAAUGUGAUAAUUUCUUUCUGCAAAGUGCCAAAUAGUAUUUUAGGUUUUGUAGGCCUUAUAGUCUCAACUAUGCAACUACUCAAUUUUGCCCUUAUGGUGCAAAUGCAGCCAUUGACAAGUGGGCGUGGCCGUGUUCCAAUAAAUCUAUAUAAAAAACAGGCAAUAGACAGAUUUUAUCCAAGGGCUGUAGCAUGCCAGCCUUUGCUCUAGAACAUGUCUAACAGGUCAUCUUUUCUGAUAGGGACCUCACUCCUUCAUAAGGCAACUUGCUCCAUCUCAAGACAACUACCACUAUUUGGGGUGUUUUUUAAACCAUUCUCUUUUGUUGAAACCUCCACAACUAUAAUUUUUAAAAAUUGAUUUCAGGCUGGGUGUGGUGGCUCAUGCCUGUAAUCCCAGCACUUUGGGAGGCCGAAGCAGGCAAAUCACAAGGUCAGGAGUUCAAGACCAGCCUGGCCAACAUGGUGAAACUCCAUCUCUACUAAAAAUACAAAAAAUUAGCUUGGCAUGGUGGCGGGUGCCCAUAAUCCCAGCUACUCAGGAGGCUGACGCAGGAGAAUGGCUUGAACCCGGGAGGCAGAGGUUGCAAUGAGCCGAGAACGUGCCACUGCAGUCCAGCCCAGGCGACAGUGUGAGAUCCAUCUCAAAAAAAAAAAAAAUUGAUUUCAGGCUGUACUGCAUUAUGACUGCACCUGUGAAUAGCCACUGUACUCCAGCCUGGGCAACAUAGGGAGACCCUGUAUCUAAAAAAUAAAAUAAAAUUUACUACAGGUUCACAAAAGGCAUAAAGAAUAAUAUAAUGAAUAUCCAUAAGAAAUGACACAUUUCUCAAAUAGCCAAAGCCUCCUAUAUAUCUUCUCUUGUUUAUCAUUCAUAGGUAUGUAUUUAUUCCUGUGCUAGUAAUUUGCAUAUUGUUAAGCAAUAUAAAAUGUUUUGUAAAUGGUGUCAUCGUACUACAUAUGUAUUCCUUUAAAACUUGUUUUCUUUUUUGUUGUCACUGGCUUUUGGUCUCUCCUGCAUGUUGGAACCAAUCAUUUCAAUCCAGCCUUCUCCCUUCUUUCAAUCCUAGCCCAGGCUAGGGCCGUGUUCACUUUCUUAGGAGAUCCCUCAUGGAAUCAAACCUCUGACUGGCAAGCAGAUAAUCCAGGUCUCCCUACAUCCUGUCUUUGUACAGUUGGUCCCUUGAACCCCCUAUGAAACCCUACUCUAUUUCAUUUUAUCAGUUUAGCACAGGGUCCAAACCAGGGUGAUUCUGAAUCUUAAUUAUGUCCCUCCUGAUUUUGUGUCUUCUUUCAAGAUACUGAUAAGCUAUUUGGACCAGGGCAAAAGACUGAGGCAUAGCAUGUUUCCAGGUUGACACUGAUCUGUUAAUAAACCUUCUCCAAGUAUAUUUCACCACGUUGUAGACCCACCUGACUGUACAGACAGCUGGCAUUUUUCUAUCUUGUUAGGAAGGAUCUUAUUCAAUAGCAAUAAAUAAAUAAAUAAAUAACACCUUUCAUGUGCAAAGGGUUGUGGGUGACACAGAGAUAAAACAGAUGUGAAUUCUGCUCUUAAAAAUGCUUGGCUAUUAGGUGAAACAAAAGGCCUACCUAAAAAAUAGCAAUGCAGGAAAUGCUAUGAGACUUCCACAAACAUAUCACUGAAAUCAAGAUACUAAUAUCCACCGGCCUAGUUACCCCAUCAAAAAGGAAAACACAUUUUUUUUGAUAACUUUCUGUGAAUCUAUAAUCAUUUCCCAAAUAAAAUGCUCACACACAAAAAAGGAAAACAGGUUUAAGCAGAUGAUGUGACUAUUUGUCUCUAAGAAAACAGAGACUCCUUCCUUUUCAAUAAAUGUUUCUAACCCAUCUGUUUAAAAGUCAAUUCCAGAAUUUUGUCAGGAAUUAGCAUCAAUUUUACCUGCAAUUGUGAGGAUCUUGUCUUGUCUUUUUCCAUUUCAGAAAGUCAGGGUAAUAUCUACCCUUCUUUAGUGUUCUAUUCCCGUCAUUCUCUAAGAGUAAUAGUACAGGCACACCUCAUUGUAUUGCACUUUGCAGAUAUUGCCAGAUAUUGCACUUUUUACAAAUUGAGGGUUUGUGGCAACCCUACAUCAAUCAAGUCUAUCAGUGCCAUUUUUCCAACAGUAUGUGCUCACAUUGUGCCUCUGUCACAUUCUGGUAAUUCUCACAAUAUUCCAAACUUUUUAAUGAUUAUUAUAUGUUAUGGUGAUCAGUGAUCUUUGAUGUUACUAUUGUAAUUGUUUUGGGGUGCCACAAACCAUGCUCAGACAUGAAAGUGAAAUUAAUCAAUAAAUGUUGUGUGUGUUCUGACUGUUCCCCCA